GUGCAACGGCCGUUAGAGGAGCUGAGGGAGGGAACCACCGCUCACCGCAGACGUGGUGGCUGCAGUCAGUCUUCCCGAGUGAGGGAUUUCGCCGCCCGCUUUCAGGCCCGUGUAAGUUUUCCUCCUUCGGGAGCCUCAGUCCUAGUGGCCGACCUUGCCUCUCCUCCCAUAGCUCCGGCGAAGCCUCAGACGCUCGCGACCUGCCACCGUGAGGGGCCGGGGAGAGCGAAGCGCAUGCGCCUCGGCUCCGAAGCCAGUGCCCCGGCAUACGCCCUCUCGCGUCCCAUUCCCCUCGCUUCCCCCGUUGCCUUGCUUUGCCGUCCGUGGUUCACCCCACGGCAGUCACUUUACCUGCGUGCCAGGCCCUGUGCCGAUAGCCAGGGACACAGCGAGCGGCGCAUUCCUUGCCCUUGCGGAGCGCACAGCCCUGGGAGUCGACGUUAAGCGGGUGUGGAAUUGCUGAGUCAUAGGGUAACUCGGAGUUCUCCUUCUGUCACCGUAUUUUCAACUUGUCUGAAUUUAGAAACACCUUAGAAUCCAGUGCGCCUACCAUUUUGUUAUCCUUUAAAGAAAGGAGUGAAGAAAAGGAUUUUGAUAUUGACAAGAAAGGAAAUCACUAGUAAGGAGUUGGCUUAAAUAACUGUGAUUGAUGGCCAUGCAGGAGAAAUAUCCAACUGAGGGGAUCUCUCACGUCACUUCACCGAGUUCCGAUGUGAUUCAGAAGGGCAGUUCCCUGGGGACUGAAUGGCAGACCCCAGUUAUCUCGGAGCCCUUUCGGAGCCGCUUCAGCCGCUGUUCAAGUGUAGCCGACAGUGGGGACACAGCCAUUGGUACAUCAUGCUCAGAUAUUGCGGAGGAUUUUUGCAGCUCAAGUGGCAGUCCUCCUUUCCAGCCCAUCAAAAGCCACGUAACCAUUCCAACAGCCCAUGUGAUGCCUUCUACUUUAGGGACCUCUCCUGCCAAGCCAAAUUCUACACCUGUUGGACCCUCUUCCUCUAAACUCCCUUUGUCAGGGUUGGCUGAAAGUGUGGGAAUGACAAGAAAUGGAGACCUCGGUGCAAUGAAACAUUCUCCAGGCCUAUCUAGAGAUCUCAUGUAUUUCUCUGGUGCUACUGGAGAAAAUGGAAUUGAGCAGUCCUGGUUUCCAGCAGUGGGCCAUGAAAGACAAGAAGAGGCGAGGAAGUUUGAUAUUCCUAGCAUGGAAUCUACCCUCAAUCAGUCGGCAAUGAUGGAGACACUUUAUUCAGAUCCUCACCACCGAGUCCGCUUCCACAACCCAAGAACCAGCACAAGUAAGGAGUUGUACAGAGUGUUGCCUGAGGCCAAGAAGGCACCGGGCAGCGGGGCAGUGUUUGAGCGGAAUGGACCACAUUCUAAUAGCAGUGGGGUCCUCCCUUUGGGACUCCAGCCUGCUCCCGGGCUCUCCAAGCCUCUGCCCUCUCAGGUGUGGCAGCCGAGUCCUGACACUUGGCAUCCCCGAGAGCAAUCUUGUGAACUCAGCACUUGUCGGCAGCAGCUGGAAUUGAUUCGUUUACAGAUGGAGCAAAUGCAGCUUCAGAAUGGAGCCAUCUGCCACCAUCCUGCUGCUUUUGGUCCUUCACUGCCCAUCUUAGAGCCAGCACAGUGGAUCAGCAUCUUGAACAGUAAUGAACACCUUCUGAAGGAAAAAGAGCUUCUCAUUGACAAGCAGAGGAAACACAUCUCUCAGCUGGAGCAGAAAGUGCGAGAGAGCGAACUGCAAGUCCACAGUGCCCUCUUGGGCCGCCCUGCCCCCUUUGGUGAUGUCUGCUUGCUGAGGCUACAGGAAUUGCAGCGAGAAAACACUUUCUUACGUGCACAGUUUGCACAGAAGACAGAAGCCUUGAGCAGAGAAAAGAUUGACCUUGAAAAGAAACUCUCUGCUUCUGAAGUUGAAGUCCAGCUCAUCAGAGAGUCGCUCAAAGUGGCGUUGCAGAAGCAUUCUGAGGAAGUGAAGAAACAGGAAGAAAGGGUCAAAGGUCGUGAUAAACAUAUCAAUAAUUUGAAAAAGAAAUGCCAGAAGGAAUCAGAGCAGAACCGGGAGAAGCAGCAGCGUAUUGAGACCUUGGAGCGCUACCUGGCUGACCUGCCCACACUGGAAGACCAUCAGAAGCAGAGCCAGCAGCUUAAGGAUUCUGAGUUGAAGAGCACAGAGCUGCAGGAGAAAGUGACUGAGCUGGAGAGUUUGCUGGAGGAGACCCAGGCAAUCUGCAGAGAGAAGGAGAUUCAACUGGAAAGCCUGAGGCAGAGAGAAGCAGAAUUCUCCUCCGCUGGACAUAGCCUGCAAGAUAAACAGUCUGUGGAGGAGACCAGUGGAGAAGGUCCAGAAGUGGAAAUGGAGUCCUGGCAGAAGCGAUACGAUUCGCUCCAAAAGAUUGUGGAGAAGCAGCAGCAGAAGAUGGAUCAGUUGCGCUCACAAGUACAGAGCCUAGAGCAGGAAGUGGCUCAAGAAGAAGGAACAAGCCAGGCCCUGAGAGAGGAGGCCCAGCGAAGGGAUUCAGCCCUGCAGCAGCUGCGCACAGCCGUGAAGGAGCUUUCAGUGCAAAACCAGGACUUGAUUGAGAAGAAUCUGACACUCCAGGAACACCUGCGCCAGGCCCAACCAGGGUCUCCACCUUCACCAGACACGGCCCAGCUGGCACUUGAGCUGCACCAGGAGUUGGCCAGUUGCCUUCAAGAUCUGCAGGCUGUCUGUAGCAUUGUGACCCAGAGGGCCCAGGGCCAUGACCCCAAUCUCUCCCUGCUCCUGGGCAUUCACUCACAGCACCCAGAGACUCAGCUAGAUUUGCAGAAGCCAGAUGUGAUCAAGAGGAAACUAGAAGAGGUUCAACAGCUGCGUCGUGACAUUGAGGACUUAAGGACCACCAUGUCAGACAGAUAUGCCCAGGACAUGGGAGAAAACUGUGUCACACAGUGAGGAAUUCUGGGGGAUUCCCCCAGGGAGGAGCUGGGCUGCUGAGAGCCUAGUCCAGCAGGUUUCUGCCCUGACAUUCUCUUGUCUGCUAUUCCCAGAGAGGUCUCAGAGGGGAGGGGAGAGCCUGCAUCUGGGGGCCAAGGGCUGAUUAGGGAACUGUGUCCUACCCACACUGGCAUGUUGGAUUACGUUUGUCCUGUUAAUUCACUCUAGACGGUGAGUUACUAAUUAACUUUUGGCAGGUACAACAGAUAAGUCCUCACAAACUGUUCCCAGCCCUAGGCUGACAUGAGAGACGAACAGGCUGUCCACCUUUCUUCUCCAUCCAAUGGGAUGGAUCCAUGUUCAUUCCCACUUCACACCUUGGUCCUGCUGAUUAGAGAGCUCAUCAGAGGGGCCUGGAAAGGCUGAGCAAGUACCAGUGACAAUGGCCAUUUAAGAAUUCUCAGGCCCCAUGUGCCAGCCUUCUUGGGAACUGAGCUGGCUUUCUGGGUUUUCUCAUGCCUGGUCUUACUGCUUCUUCCUCAGGGCUCUUGUUCUCCCAGAAGCCUCAGGGUAAUGUGUUGGUUAGCACGUAACUACUAGGAUUGGGGCCCUAGGGAUUAUAGCCAGGACUCUAAUCUGCCUACCAUGCCAUUUAACAAGAGAUCCCACUCUCCAGCUGCCUUGUGUCCCUAGGGUCCUGGCCAUGUGUUUAGUGUGCUAAACUUUCUCCUUUGUUCUCAGGCCUUCCAGGUAGUCCCCUUCCUGGACUUAAGAGUGCAAACUCUUCUCUGUGGUUCUAGCCUUGGGCAGAAUUAUAUCCCAGAGACCACAGAGCAACUGUCAAGCUGCUUACCCCCUCACCCAGGGCUACAGCCUGUGCCCAGCCCUCUAAUUUGUGCCUCUCUUGUGUUGGGGGUGGUGGGGGUUAUUCCUUUCCCUUUCCUGCUCUGGCCUCCUUGAAAGUUCAGAGUACCCAGUACAAGUCAGCUUUAAAGUACAGCUUUUAGUGUUUCCUGGGUUGUUUCUCUGGGGCUUUAGUGAGGGACCUUUGCCCUCUGGUUUUUCUUGCCUCCUGGUUUAGGGAGCAUCUCACACUUGUUAGUAUCUGGUUGUUGGGCCAGCCGUGCCUCCUCUAGAUCUGGAGCCAGGCCAGGCAGGGGCCACGUGUGGGCCAGUCAGCCACUACAAGAUUUUUGCUAAGCUUUGGGCUGUUGGCAGCAUCUUGGACCUCAUGCCUGGGCCUGAAUGAGGCUCUUUCUUAAGUGUUUUUACAAGUUUGUGUUUUAUUUAUGGAGUGACUUAUCCCUUCCAUUCAGAGCAGCCCCACCCAGCCAGCCCUUCAGCCUCUGGGCUCCUGCUGCUUAAAGGCAGAGCCGCCUGGUUGGUCUCCACCCUGUGCAUUGGGAGCCCAGCCACCAUGCUGACGGGUAUUUUUCCUCAUAAAGUUUAUAACCAGUUAUUUAUAUGAAUCUUUGUUAUGUCCAUUUGUUUGUAUUGCGUAUUUUGAUUAUAAAAUAAAGUAUCUUAACAGAC